GCACUUUGAGAGUUUUCAGCUGGGUUCUCAGGCUGCGUUCACCCGUCGACUUGCUCCAGGCCAAACCAGAUUUUGAAAAGGAAGGCAACUUCUUUUUCGCGGCAAACCCUUAAACCCACGCACCUUCUCAAAACUCUGCCCUUCUCAACCCCUGCGCUAGAGUAGGCAGGGCAGAAGGUGCUGAGGAGAGGCUCAGAAGGGGCGGUGGGGACGAUCCCCUUUCGAACUGCAUUUGUAGCUGCCAAGGAGUAGCCAACAAGCACCAGAUUUAUGUGCACUUUGAAAGAAGCACCUUCACCAUUGGCUUUUUAAGCGGCGCUGUCGCUAGGGAGCGGCUGGUAGGGCGAGCAGCCUCGGGGAGCAGCCCGGGCUGUUUGUUCCGUCACCGGGGAAAGGAGGUACACACAGUCGCGCGCGCACGGACACACACACACACGCACGCACGCACACACACCGGUGGCGAGUUCGAGCCCCGCGGCCCCUGUCCGCCCGCGUGCGCCCCUCGACACAGCUCGCCUCCCGCCCCCUGAUUCCUGCUGCUGCCGCCCAGAGGAGAAAGGAACCUCUGCCUCGAAUUUCCCCACUGCGCCGGGCGCUGCGGAGAGCGGCGAGGGUGGGCGCGAGGCGGAGAACGCGAUGAAUGAGUUCUCCCCUCGCCUCGGAGUUGUCUGAGUUGGCGGCGCUGCGCCCAGGCUUCCGGCUCUCAGCGCCCCACGCGCGCGUGGCUCCCCGGGCUGCCACCCACGCCCGCGGCCGGGGCCGAGCCAGCCACGCAGGGCAGCCGAGGCUCCGGAGCUCCUGUCCCGGCCCCAGUCCGGGUAAAAGGAGGGUUGUCCCCAGCGGAGGCGCACAGCCGCGCGUUCUCCCUGCACUCUCUUCGCGGUCCCAUCUGUUCCCCAUGGCGUCUCAUCCGCAAACCCGGAUCCAGGCUUACCUGGAGAAGAACAAGAUCGGUCCCCUGUUUGAGGAAUUAAUGACCAAGUUAAUAACUGAGACACCUGACCAGCCAAUCCCAUUUCUCAUUGACCAUCUUCAGUCUAAACAAGGGAACCGUGGACAACUUCAAAGAACUUUGUCUGGAUCUGCAGCUCUAUGGGCAGAAAGUGAAAAAUCAGAAUCCAAAGGAACAAGAAGGGAUUUCAGAAGCUAUGAUAAACCUUGGCAAUUAAAUGCAAAGAAGCCUAAAAAAUCAAAAAGUGACCUUGCUGUGUCUAAUAUUUCUCCACCAUCACCGGACUCCAAAUCAUUGCCAAGGUCAGUAGAGCAUCCAAAGUGGAACUGGAGGACUAAACCACAAAGCCGUGAUUUUGAUGAAUUGAAUCACAUCCUUCAGGAGAGCAAGAAGCUGGGGAAAGCCCUUGAGAAUCUCUCUCGAAGUAUUGCAAUUUCAGAUGAACUCGAUAAGGAAACAGUGACAUUUAAUUCUUCUCUUCUGAGGCCCCGUGUGAUUGGAGAAUGGAUUGGUAGAGAAGAAAAUGAUGCUGAUCCCCUAGCUGCUGAAAUGCUACAGCCUCCAAUUCCAAGAAGCAAAAAUGACCAAUGGGAAAGUGAAGAUAGUGGCUCUAGUCCUGCAGGAAGCUUAAAGAUGGAGCCUAAGAACAAAGGAUUAAAACAGCAGCAACAGCAACAUAAGAAACUCCUGGCCGCAAUGCUCUCUCAAGAUUCUUUUGAGUCCAUCCACAGCCCUACCCCAUCUGUAACAGAAGAAGAUAUUGAUAAUGAAGAUGAUGCAAUGGAAUUGCUGGGUAAUUUUAAAAAUUAAUAAUUUCUCAUUUUCUUCUUUGACAUUGUAAAAAAAACGUGUGGUGAUUAAGAGAUUUUAAAAGUUUUGAAUAGCCUUGUCUUAGGGAAAAGAAACCAUUUAGUACAUAUUUUAUUUACAUUAGACUCACAUAAAGUUGCAUGUAAGAACUAAAUUGAAAUACCCUAAGCAUAUGAAUAUUUAUUAGACUGUAUUUUGUGCUUUGUGUAUGCUGCACUUUACCUUCUGACUACGUAAUGAAGCGUUAUUCUGUGUGCAACUGUGAUCAAAAUUCAAGUCUGUCUGCUUUAUUCUCUGAUAAUAAUUGCCUUGUUUACAUCUAUUGUCUAUAAAAUAUACCCAAAGUACAUAUUUCAGCCCUCACUCCAAAAUGUCUACCUUUUAUUUUGAGGAUGCUUUAGAAAAAUAGAAUAAAGUUGAAAGGGGCAGAUAGUAAAUUCAGGUUUUAUGUUUUCCGUAAAUGACGGGAAAGUUUGCAGAGAUUUCAAAGUUUCUUCAGGCCUGUUACUUUCAUGAAACCUUAUUAAUCUUGUAUAUGUAGGAUAUCUUUUUAUAUUUUUUAAUGUAGUAUAUGUAUGUUUUUGCUUCAUCAGAAAUCUCUUCAUAUAAAUUUUUAAACUGAACUUCUCUUUGGAACAUCAUUUUUCUGAAGAAAGAAAAUGAAAUGUUAUUUCAGAGUGAUCCACAUAUAAAACAAUGAGUUUUGAAGUCAGUGGUAUCAAUUAUUCUGCUACAAAUAAAGAGUAUGAUUUUCAAAUACUUUAUAACAAUAUGCUGUUGUAUUUUAUUUAGAAAGAGAAUAAAUAAUAUAAUUAUUUGAAAGCCUUAAACACGUUUUACAUAUAGAAUAUGGAAUCUCAGAAAAAUAUAGGCCAUUUUCUGAAGUUUUUGUUAAAAAUGAGAUUCCUUGGUUUUAAGUGUUUAUGGCAGUAAAAUACUAUCAUUAUAAAAAAUGAUAUAUUGCUUAUCAUUUUUGCAUAGGCCUACAAAGGUGUUAUUUGGUCAAUGGUGACAGGUUUGAAAGAUGUUUUCUGAUGCUGUAAAAACUGCAUUCAUGCUAACAUUAAGGAGAUUGUAUCAUGGCGUUUUCAUUACAUGCUGUUGGUCCCUUCCAAUUGGGUCUUUUCCUCACCUCCAAAUCAUUAACAUGGCAGACGUGCCCUAUGUGGCAGUGGUAGCUUCAUUCAACAAACAUUUACUGAGCACUUACUCUAUGCUAAGCACUUGGCUGGGGUCUGGGAACAUAAAAAUAAAAUCAUUGUGAUCUGUGUUUGAAGGAAUUUUACAUUGUAAUGUUCAAGAUACAAUACGUCACUACCUGUGCUAACUGCGCUAAUUGGAUGAAGCACACAGUUGUGUAUAGGGGUAACACCUAAAGCAGAGGUAAGGGACAGUGACCCAGGAAUGUUUCCUAGAGAAGCCGAUUACUCUGGCUAGUCCUGAAAAGCAAAUAGAUGUAAGCUCAGCAGGUGGGGUGUGGUCAUUGUAGGUUUGCUCACGUAGGUAUGGGCUGUUUUGCGAUUGUGCUCCAUAACUAUACCUGUAAAUGGUUCCUCUGCUUUGGACAGUAACAGGGAAGGGGCAACUGAGAUCCAGGGUUUCUUUCAGGAGAUGCAGUUGUCCACUCCAUGCUGGUACUCCCUAGAUCUCAGCUGCCCUGACUGAAGGUUCUAGUCUCCCAAGCUGAAGACCGAGGAUUGAGUCUUGGAGACUAUCUAAUGAUGAGCAAUUAAUAACUAGUCCUCAUUAAUUCUUUUUUUAGACAUUUUAGCCUGUGGUCUGAGCAAGUUUAAUAAUAAGAGAUAGUUGAAGGUUUGGACUUUCUUCAUGUAAUUCCACAUAUCUCAGCACAGGUGGCAAGCAGUGUAAUAAUGUUGGUCUCUAGGUCAUGAGAUUAUCCUCUUAUAGCUUGGAAUGUUACAAGUCCACUGGACUUUAUCUUAAAAUAAUGCCAUAUUCAAUUUCUUGUUUUUGAAAUGGAUUCCAGCAAAAUGUAUGUGAUUGUGUCUAUUUCAGAAAAAUAUAAAUGCUAAGUUCUUGGAAAUUUAUGUGAAAUCUAAUUUUAUAGAGUUUAUAUAGAAUCAUUGUAAGAUGCAAUAGAGACAUCUGGUAUUUAAAAUCUUUUUGAAUCUACAUUUUGUAGAUGUGUGUGCUAUAGCUUAUGUGUUUGUAAAUGUUUAACUUGUCUUUGUUAUCUAUACCAAGAUAUAACUGGCUGAAAAAUAUUUAUUAUGCAUGGAAAGCACUCUGUAAACCUUGUGAAGUGAUAAAUAAGUGAAAGGUAUAAUUGUUAGUUGACAUUAAUAUAAAAAAGGAUUAUUCUUCAAUAAAAUUGGUUGAUUUGAAGGGAAAAAAUCCUUUUAGUUGAACUAGUAGAAGUUAGUAAUAACUAUUGACUCUUGUUUUGUUUAUUAAGGAAACUAGCAUUGUUAAUAUAUACUGAUUAAUAUUUAAUUAUUCACAGUUGUUUAAUUAUAUAUUUGUGGAUUUCUUUUCUAAAUGUUUUAGGCAUAUGAAAAUAUUAUAGUACAACACCUGUAAUUUUUAAGUAGAUCAAAUAUUUUCUGUAAGAUUGCUUUAAAUGCUCCUUAUAAAUUCACAUUGCAAAAGUAACUUAAUAUGGAAUUAACACUUGUCAGAUAAUAAAACAGCCAAACUUGUGAAUUUUUAAGAUAUAAUCAUUUUAAGCACCUCUGAAAUUGGUGCUGUAAUUAUAGAAGAUACUGAGUAAAGUAUCUGCCAAGUCAUCUCAUGCUCAAAUAUAAGAUAUUUUCAAAUAUUUUAGUACAAAUAUUUUAGUAAUCGUUCUGGCAAUUAAUGACCACUAUGAAAAAAAGGUUAUAGAAAAUCUUCACAUAUUUUUUAAAAUUAAUAAAAUAAAUGAUUUUCAAAAAUGGAAUGACAAGUUACAAUGGUAGAAUGAGAGAUUUAUUGCUGGGCAUAGUGGCUUAAGCCUGUAAUACCAGCACUUUGGGAGGCUGAGGUGGGUGGAUUGCUUGAGCCCAGGAAUUUGAGACCAGCCUGGGAAACAUGACGAAACCUCGUCUCUACAAAAAAUACUUAUAUUAGUCAAGUGUGGUUGCAUGCACCUAUAGUCCCAGCUACUGGACUGAGUCUGGAAGGUCGAGUCUGCAGUGAGCUGUGGUCAUGCCACUGUAGUCCAGCCUGGGUGACAGAGGGAGACCCUAUCUCAAAAAAAAAAAAAAAAAAAAAAAAAGAAGAAAAAGAAAAGAUCUAUAAAAAUCCCUGUAUAUUUUACUACAUUAAUUAUCAGAGAACAUUUGAGGAACUUCGUUAGUUUAAAAGAUAUUUCACCUUGGAAACAUGUGCCCAUUUUUCUUACAUUAGAUGCAUUUUAAUCUUAUUCUUGUUGAAAGGCGAGUUUCAGUCACGUUUUUGAUUAUUCUCUUUAUGAUUGAUAUUCAUUUAAAAAUAUCAGUAUUAUUUGAAAGAUAUAACUACUUUUCUUAUACAUUCUAAUAUGGGUAUUACUAUCCCAUACAAUUUGUAAAAGUUUAUAAAAAAUGUAUUAUGCUUUCUCAGAAUUGAUGAUGAGGCAAGUAUAUAAAAAUCAAAUUCCAAAGAUGCUAAAAAGGAAAACAAUAUUAAUUAUGUUUUAUACUUUUUGGUCUUAGCCUAUAAUUAUAUAAAAUCCAAAAUCAAAAGUAAAAUUACAUUGCGACAAGGUGAUUGCAAGUACAUUUUAUCUGUUUUAAAAUGAAUAAUCAAGAACAAGUGUAAUUAUACUGGGAUUCUUUGCUGAAUAUAGUCAUUGAGUUUCUAUUACCUCAAUAUGUUACCAAAUUUUGUAAAAUAAAAACAAUUUACUAGAAGGAGUUAAUACAUUAAGGUGAUCAUUUGACACUUUCUUUCUUAUAUUCUGAUCAACUUUUAUAAAGUAAAUAUUCACUCUUUGUUCUGUUUUUUAAAUUGGAGGCUUCUUAAAGAAGAAUGUGCCCACAUUGGCAAAAUAAGAACAAGCAUUUUGCCUAAUGAGAAAUGAAUGCUGUCACUGAAUGAUGUAAAAUUUCUUUAAAAAGGAGAGAGAGGGAGCACUAAAUGUUUAAAGAAAAAUCUACCUACCUAUCCAUGUACCUAUAUUUUAAUAAAGUAUGUAAAAUAAUCUAAAACACAAGGGACUAUACAUAGAAACUCUUUUUAUCUCUUUGUUUCUUUUGAUCUUUAGAAUAUUGCUCAUUGGAAGUAAUCAGGAUAACAGAAAAGUUAUCACCUUAAAAUGAAUGUUCUUCAUAAAAAAGAUUAUUCAUAAGAAAUCUAAGGACUUUCUUUUUAUUUUCUUUUUUUUUUUAAAGAGAUCAAGUCUUGCUUUGGCUAAUGCAGUUUGUAUCACUUUCUUAUGUCCUCCUUCCUGAUAUAUUUUAUAGGAGCACUUGAAAAAUGAACUGCUUAGAGUAGAAAAAAUCACAUAAAUUAUAAAGUAAUUCUAGCAUAGACUUGAGAAAAUGGUUUCUUUAUGAUUCAUUUUCAUCAUAUUAUCAUGUUAAAAAGCUUUAUUUAGGAUUCUUUCUUUGCUUUUGCUAAAUGUAUCUCAGUCCCUUUUAUUACCUUCUAGAUUUACUUGUUUUGUGUUUAGAAUUGUUUUGUUUUUCAUACCCUUCAUUCUUCACUUUUGUUUUUUUCAGCAAAAUAUCAAAACAUUUGCAAAUCGUAGAGAUUAUCCUUUAAAUAAAUACAAAUCUGCAUGCCACCAAAAUAUAUACAUCAUCCUAUGUGAUUUACUUUUAUGGUGUUUAGUAAGAAAUAUUGCUUUAUUUUCUUGUAAAAAAUUUCCAGUGGUAAAAAUAAAUCAACAUAGUAGAAUAAACGUCAAUAGUUUGAAAAUGAAAUCUAAACCCAUAAACAAAUUAUUGACAAAUGCCUUUUAUCUCAAUUAUACACCUAUUGGAAAAUUUCUUUAUAAGACACAGCCAUUUCCAAUAUAUUUGUGAAAAGAGUUGUUUAAAACCUAUUUAUCACUUUGAAUAAGUUCCACGUUUUUUGACACAUACCAAUAACAUAGAAUAAUAUAUUUUUUCUUGUUUAUGUUAUAGCUUUUCACUGAGUACCUUGUAAAGGCAUGAGACACAGUGUGAUUGGCAUAUGUGGUGGUGUUAGUGGUAUAUGGCCAAAGCACCAGCUUAUACUCUAAUGACCCAGGUCUAGACCUCAUGCUACCUCUUGCUAAUAUUGUCCCCUCAGGUACACGUAAUUAAUUGUAAAGUGCUGGUGACUACAUAUGACCUUCCUACUCAACAGGGAUGUUGAGAGGAUAAAAAAAAAAUGAGAUAUUUCUCUAAAGUGCUUUUUUUUUUUCUUUUUGUCAUGGCUAACAGGAAUAUUUGACAAAAGACAAUAGAAUUUCUAUACAAAACUUUUCUUCUAGAUAAAUUUAUAUCCUUGAACCCAGAUACAUUUUGUAUGCUACAGACAAAGGAAAAAAAAAGCUUUCUUUAGCUUUGGGAAGUUGCCUAAAAACAGCAAAAAUGUAUGUUUCCCACAACACAAUAAAAUUAAAGGCUUGAAAAGAUAAGAGGUAAAGCUAUAUGUUUUUGCAAGCCAAAAUGUUGGCUAUACCAACACAAAGCACUAAAUUUUUCAUUUUUAACUUGGAUAUUAAAGCAAGGAUAGAUGAUUUGGUUAAGGAUGUAUAGAAAAUUAUUCUACUGUCUUUCAUUUUCCUCUGUGUAAAUGUAUAAUUCCUAGGAGGAAAAGAAAAAUGUUUUCUGCCUACAUAUGUAUCUCUAGUAGCAAAAGUUGGGCUUAGGGUAGGAAUAAGGUGGAAAGACAAGGAGAUAUAGAGAAAUUAGAAAUUUGUACUAUAUGUUUACAUGCUUAUGUAAAUAAAAUUAUAAAAGUGUUGAAAAUCUGUUCUUAAAAAUUUCUUGAAUUAUAUUUAUAAAUAUGAAAAUGUUUGAAGCAGCACAAUUUGAUGGUUUCACAUUAAUUCACUGUGUAAACAAACCUAAACUAAAUUGAAAAGCAGUGUUACAUAUUAUUAAGGUAUUGUUGCUUUUGAAAUAAACUUGCCCACUUCAAAUGCUU